GCUCCGCGCUUCUGCUUCCGGCGGCGCUGGUGGUGGCGCGCGGCGCGGCGCGGCGAUGGCGGCGGGUGGCAGCGAUCCGCGGGCUGGCGACGUAGAGGAGGACGCCUCACAGCUCAUCUUUCCUAAAGAGUUUGAAACAGCUGAGACACUUCUAAAUUCAGAAGUUCAUAUGCUUCUGGAACAUCGAAAGCAGCAGAAUGAGAGUGCAGAGGACGAACAGGAGCUCUCAGAAGUCUUCAUGAAAACAUUAAACUACACAGCCCGUUUCAGUCGUUUCAAAAACAGAGAGACCAUUGCCAGUGUUCGUAGCUUGCUACUCCAGAAAAAGCUUCAUAAGUUUGAGUUGGCCUGUUUGGCCAACCUUUGCCCAGAGACUGCUGAGGAGUCCAAGGCUCUAAUCCCAAGCUUGGAGGGACGGUUUGAAGAUGAGGAGCUGCAGCAGAUUCUUGAUGAUAUCCAGACAAAGCGCAGCUUUCAGUAUUAAUCUCCAAACAUCACUGCUGCUCGGAGAAACCACAUCCCCAGGCAUAACACCACCUUCCCACUGUCUGGGGCUGACUUGCACAGAAAUUCUGUUGAAGACAGUUGAGAAUUCCUUUGGAGAAAACAGCCCAGCUUGGCGUGGGGUUAGGUUGCUGUUUCAAAUAACUCACAGGCCCAGGUGACAUGGAAUCUUGGAGCAGCCUUGUGCAGUGGCAGCCAGUGGCUUCCUGAACGUGCCUCUGCGAAGUGUGAGAUGAGGGGUCACAUAACCACACUGUUGACUACCUCAUUCCUGGUUUUUGGCCUCCACAUCAUCUUUUUUCUUAAUAUUUCAUGUUUUAAUUUCAGGGUGUUUAUACUUUUUGAAACUAGACCAGAAGAUAGUAGACUUUAUAGAGAAAGACCAGUUUUACCUAGAUACUAAAGGAAGAAUUAAACCGCUGUUAGUUUGAAAUGCUUUUUUUUUUUUUUUUUAAAUGGAGAUAGGGUCUUAACUCUUGUCCAGGCUGGAGGAGUGCAGUCGUACAGUCAUGGCUCACUGAAGUCUUGACCCCGCUGCCUCAGCCUCCCAAAUAACUGGGGCCACAGGUGUGCACCACAACUCUCAGCUAAUUUUUAAAAUUUUUUAUAGAGGUGGGGUUUUACUAUGCUGUCCAGACUGGUCUUAAACUCCUGGGCUCAAGUGAUCCCCCUGCCUUGGCCUCCCAAACUGGUGAGAUUACAGGCAUGAGCCACCACAACUGGCCUGAAAUUCUUAAAGGAUGGGAGUGUCGAUGACAGCACCUUGGCAUCGUUGUGCCUAACCUGGGAGACGGAAGAAGCACGCCAUGGGAAGUGUUUACACUUGGGGACAAGUGCUAAGUAUUGUGGAGCCCAUAGCCCCUUGAGAUAGAUGGCUACUUUGCCUUUCUUCUUGAACUGUCUUGCAGAAUGUGGAUUUGGGGUAAGUGGUCUUGAAGGAUUCAUUUAGUCACCCUCAAAUUAAGAUUUUUACUUCAUCUUUCUUGGGCCUGCACCUCCAAGAUAACAAAGAAGAAGCAAUGGUCGUGCCAAAGAGGUCCACAACCAGGUGUGCACUGUUCACUGCAGCCCAUUUGCUGUAUGAACUGUGGUUGUUGUGUGCCCAAUGACAAGGCUACUAAGAAAUUCAUCAUUUGAAACGUAGAGGCCGCAGCAGUCAGCGAUGUUUCUGAAAUGAGCAUCCUUGACGCCUGUGUACUUCCCAGGCUGGAUGUGAAGCUACAUUACCAUGUGAGUUGUGCCAUUCACAGCACAGUGGUGAGGAAUUGAGCUCAUGAAGCAGGCAAGGACCGAACACCUCCACCCCAACGUAGACCUGCAGGUGCUGCCCCAUGACCUCCACCAAAGCCCAUAUAAGGAGCGGAGUUGUUAAGGACUGAAGAAAAACUUCUCUGGAGAAAAAUAAAAUUGCAAUUCUACUUAAAAAAAUUUUUUUUUUUUUUUACUUCAUAGGCCAGGCUUGAAGUUCUGAACACUUUGAAGUCUCCAAUUAUGAGAGAUCCAGUCUAAGCCUCUGGCCUGCUAAUUAGCAAUAAGUGCUUUAUUUGGAAGGAGGGAGUCAUCCACUCUUGAGCCACUGCAGUGAAGUCACUUGAUCUCAGUCUGGGGGAAAACACUUCAAUAGCUAAACAUUCUAGCUUUGAUUUUUCUGAAGGGAAUACACUUGUUUUCAAUUUUGGGGUUUUUCUUUGGGGCACUUGCUUGACUCUGUAUGAACUUGUGAUCCAAGGAAAAAGGAGAAAGAACAGUGUUGGCUUUUAAAAUCAGGAUGGUUUUAUGUUUGCUACGAAAUAAGGCAAGAAUAAAAAAUUCUUAUUUUUAUUUAUUUAUUUAUUUUUUGAGAUAGAGUCUGGCUGUGUUGCCCAGGAUGCAAUGGCGCAAUCUUGGCUCACUGCAACCUCUGCCUUCUGGGUUCAAGUGAUUCUCCUGCCUCAGCCUCCCAAGUAGCUGGGAUUACAGGUACCUGCCACCACGCCUGGCUAAUUUUUUGUGUUUUUAGUAGAGACAGGGUUUCACCACGUUCGCCAGGCUAGUCUUGAACUGACCUCAAGUGAUCCUCCCACCUCGGCUUCCCAAAGUGCUGGGAUUACAGGCGUGAGCCACCGGCCAAUCUUUUUAUCCUUGAGCAACUUCGCUUCUUUGAGCCUCAUUGGUGUUCUCAAUUGUGAAAUAUGGAUAAUAGUAUCUGCCCCAUGGGUAUUUUGAGAAGGUUGAAUGAACAGGAAAUUAUUACAAAGAGCCUAGAGGUGUCUGAUAUAUAGUAUGUUCCAGUAAAUGUUCACUAUUCUUAGCAUCUCAGGCAGAUGAGCUAGUAUAGAUAGAUGAUUAAGUCAGCUUGCUUCAUAGAAAUUAGUGCAAGAAUUUGUUAGCCUACCAACUGAUAGUAUCAGACUUGGAAAAUAAAUGAAAUUGGGCCAGGCGUGGUGGCUCACCCUUGUAAUCCCAGCGCUUUCAGAGGCCGAGGCAGGCGGAUCACCUGAGGUUGGGAGUUUGAGACCAUCCUGACCAACAUGGAGAAACCCCGUCUCUACUUAAAAUACAAAAUUAGCGGGGCGUGGUGGCGCAUGCCUGUAAUCUCAGCUACUCUGGAGGCUGAGGCAGGAGAAUUGCUUGAACCUGGGAGGCAGAGGGGGUGGCGAGCCAAGAUUGCACCAUUGUACUCCAGCCUAGGCAACAAGAGCGAAACUGUCUCAAAAAAAAAAAAAAAAAAAAAGUGAAAUUGCUUACCCAAAUCUACAGUUAACUUUCGUUUUUUAAUGCUUGAUGAAUUUGCAUGUCAUUCUUGGGCAGUGGCCAUGCUGUCUUCUCUGUAUUGUUCCAAUUUGGGUAUAUGUGCUGCCAAAGUGAGUACUGCAGAAUUAUUUCUUGAGAGAGGCACUUACAUGUGCUGAUUGGCACUAAAGCAGUGGAAUGGGAAGAAGAGACUUGGAAGGCAGCCCAGACGAUCCAGGCGUGUGCUAGAUGGCAACUGAGGAGCACGGUGCUACCAUCUUUACUGGUGUUUCCACCUAUGUGCCAGGGGUUCUGUGAGCUACCUGAGAAUACUGAAGUAUAUAAUGCUCUGGCACAUAGUUAGGCACUAAUCAGUGGUAUUUAUCAAGGUGAUUAAAAGCAGAUUUAAAAAGCAGCUCACAGUUGGGCGCGGUGGCUCACACCUGUAAUCCCAGCACUUUGGGAGGCCGAGGCGGGUGGAUCACCAGAGGUCAGAAGUUCGAGACCAGCCUGGCCAACGUUGUGAAACCCUGUCUCUACUAAAAAUACAAAAAUUGGCCACGUGUGGUGGCGGGCACCUGUAAUCCUAGCUACUUGGGAAGCUGAGACAGGAGAAUUGCUUGAACCCGGGAGGUGGAGGUUGCAGUGAGCCAAGAUCAUGCCAUUGCACUCCAGCCUGGGCAACAAGAGCGAGACUCCAUCUUGAAAAAAAAUAAAAUAAUAAAAAGCAGCUCAUACUAGGGAACUUGGUAAAGCAACCUCAUGCUGUUGUAGGUUGAAAGCCUGGUCAGCUAUUCUGCAAGACAGUCAAAAAUUGUUUACAGGGCUGGACAGCAUAUUGCUAUUGAAAAAUAGCUAUUAGGAGACCUUGCACAAUUUGUGAAACAUUGUUAGGCUCAUUGUACUGUGUAAAAUCAGGAAAGAAUUUGGGAACAUACUGAUACAACAAAAAGAUAGGUUGUCAAACCCUCACUUCACCAGAAAGCUAAAUUAACCAGAUAAGUCUUUCUGAAAGUUUUAGUGUCUUAGUUUGUUCCUGCGCUGUAACAGAAUACCUUAGACUGGGUAACCUAUAAAUAAUAGGAAUUUAUUUCUCACAGUUUUGGAGGCUGGCAAAUGCAAGAUCCAGGUGCUGGUACGUUCAGUGUCUGGCAAGGGCGGCUUUCUGGUCCAAGAUGGUGCCUUUUUUUCUGCAUCUUCCAUAGGGAAUGAACACUCCUUAUGGUAGAAGGGAUGGAAGGACCAGGCUUUUUUUUUUUUUUUUUUUGGAUACAGCAGGAUCUUGCUCUGUCGCCCAGGCUGGAGUGCAGUGGCAUGAUUAAGGUUCACUGCAGCCUCAAUCUCCCACUCUCCAGCGAUCAUCCCACCUCAGCCUCUUGGAUAGCUGGGACCACAGGCACGAGCUACCAUGCCUGGCUAAUUUAUUUUUUGUAGAGACGGGGUUUCGCCAUGUUGCCCAGGCUGGUCUGGAAUUUCUGACCUCUAGCAGUCCACCUGUUUCCGCCUCCCAAAUGCUGAGAUUAGAGGCAUGAGUCACUGCACCCAGCCCGCAGCCUCUUUUAUAAGGGCAUUAAUCCCCUUCAUGAGGGAUAUUCUCUCAUGACUUAAUCACCUGCCAAAGACCCCACCUCUUAAUACUACAUCAGUGAUGGGUUCAAUGUAUCAAUUGGGUGGGAGGGGGCACAUUCAGACCAUAGCAUCUAGUCAUUCUGGUUUUAUUAAGAUUUAUUAGACCUGAGGCAUGAAAAAUAGCAUACUGGAUGGGACUUCAGCAUCGAUGAGUUGCCUUAGUAAUACUGUUAAUAAAAAGCACUAAAUAUGC